AUGUAUGUGUCAAAUUGCAAUCCUUGUGCUAUUCACAGAAAAAUCAAUUAUCCAAAUACCAAACUGGAUUUCGAGCAAGUGAACAACAUAACGGAAUUCAUCUUGCUUGGCCUGACACAGAACGCAGAGGCACAGAAACUCUUGUUUGCUGUGUUUACACUCAUCUACUUUCUCACCAUGGUAGACAACCUAAUCAUUGUGGUGACAAUCACCACCAGCCCAGCCCUGGACUCCCCCGUGUAUUUUUUUCUGUCUUUCUUUUCCUUCAUAGAUGGCUGCUCCUCUUCUACCAUGGCCCCCAAAAUGAUAUUUGACUUACUCACUGAAAAGAAAACUAUUUCCUUCAGUGGGUGCAUGACCCAGCUCUUUGUAGAACAUUUCUUUGGGGGAGUUGAGAUCAUUCUGCUCGUGGUGAUGGCCUAUGACUGCUAUGUGGCCAUCUGCAAGCCCCUGUACUACCUGAUCACAAUGAACAGGCAGGUAUGUGGCCUCCUGGUGGCCAUGGCAUGGGUCGGGGGAUUUCUUCACGCUCUGAUUCAAAUGCUUUUAAUAGUCUGGCUGCCCUUCUGUGGCCCCAAUGUCAUUGACCAUUUCAUCUGUGACCUUUUCCCUCUGCUAAAACUCUCCUGCACUGACACUCACGUCUUUGGACUCUUUGUUGCCGCCAACAGUGGGCUGAUGUGUAUGCUCAUUUUUUCUAUUCUUAUUACCUCUUACGUCCUAAUCCUCUGCUCACAGCGGAAGGCUCUCUCUACCUGCGCCUUCCAUAUCACUGUAGUCGUCCUAUUCUUUGUUCCCUGUAUAUUGGUGUACCUUCGACCCAUGAUCACCUUCCCUAUUGAUAAAGCUGUGUCUGUGUUUUAUACUGUGGUAACACCCAUGUUAAACCCUUUAAUCUACACCCUCAGAAACACAGAGGUGAAAAAUGCCAUGAAGCAGCUCUGGAGCCAAAUAAUCUGGGGUAACAAUUUGUGUGAUUAG